UGCACCACUGCACUCCAGCCUGGGCCACAGAGUGACACUCUUGUCGGAAAACAAAACAAAAAGUCUCCUUAGAUUAAAACUGGAUUCCAGCCUCGGUUCCACUGGUCACCAUUCAAGUACUUUGCAUCUCUAAGUCUCUGUUUCUUUAACUUCAAAGGGAAGUUAGCAUUUUCCUUACAGAGGUGCUGAGGAUUAAAUGAGAAGAGGGUAUGAGAUUUGAGGCUGGGGAAGGAGGCAUGGGGUUCUAGGAAAGGGAGGCAGUCACUUAGGCCUGGAGUAAGGGGACAGGGGCCUGGGCAGGCGACAGAGCCCCACAGUGCUGUUGCUACCCUGUUAAUGGGCCCAGAAUCUGGAAGCCAGCCACCACAUGCCCUCACACCCAGGGUCUUCCUGCAGGUGGAGCUGAAGAGCCAAGAGGCUCAGAGUCUGCAGCAGCAGCCAGACCAUUACCUGGGUCACCUGCAGCAGUACGUGGCCACCUAUCAGCAGCAGGUGGCCGCCUAUCAGCAGCUGACCUGUGAGAAGGAGGCGCUGUACAGGCAGUGCCUGCAACAGACCCAGCUAAUGAAACAGCUGCAGCAGCAGGAAGUUUGGGGCAAAGCAGUGGCCGAGAUGGCCUGCCAAAAGUUGCAGGAGACCCAGGGGAGGGAGCUGCCAAGGAUGGGGCUGUGAGGGGGACGACCUGGCAAACUCCAUCCCUUCUCACUCUGUCCUGG